AACCCCCUCGGCCUCCCAAAGUGCUGGGAUUACAGGCGUGAGCCACUGUUUCCGGCCAGUUAUCCAGAACUGUUUAGUUAACUAGCAUUCAAGUUUAUGAAGAUUUUUGUGUAGAUGUAAUGCUUGCUUCUGCCAAGGAAUAAGAAUGUUGUAAUCCACCAUCUUUUAUUCUGGCUUUUAGGCAGCUGUUGAGGUAAACAAACUAAGUUUAAUGCUCGAAGAUAGUGUAUUCCUCAGAACUAACACAUUUGAUUUUCCAUAGGUUUAUUUUCCUUUACCUGUUCUAAUUUAACUUUUUGUAAAAUGCCACAGUCCAUUUUUAGAAAGAUUAAGGGAUAUUUCAUUAUUAUAGAUAAGUUUCUAGGUUUCUUUCAAACUUGAUAUACCUAAUAUAAAAGUUCAGAUUAUUUUUCCUCUUUAUUUUUCACUUUUUAUUCAGCCAACUGUGAUUUCUAGAAUUUUGAUUUUCAGCUUCUGAACCCCAGAAUUUCUGAAGAUGAUUAAUGACCUCCGACUAUACUAAAAGUUUUGAAAAAUUUUUUUAAAGUAAAGAAUCCUGUUGUAAUGUGAACGGUGUCUCCCUAAUUUAUGUAUUUUCAGUUUGCAUUUUCAUGAAGUGCUCAAAAUGGGACAUGUGAAAUUCUGAGAGUAGUAGUAAGAAACAUGGGAGAGUGCUAUUCCCUUCAGCAAGCUCAAGCUUUUUAUACGUUUCCAUUUCAACAACUGAUGGCUGAAGCUCCUAAUAUGGCAGUUGUGAAUGAACAGCAAAUGCCAGAAGAAGUUCCAGCCCCAGCUCCUGCUCAGGAACCAGUGCAAGAGGCUCCAAAAGGAAGAAAAAGAAAACCCAGAACAACAGAACCAAAACAACCAGUGGAACCCAAAAAACCUGUUGAGUCAAAAAAAUCUGGCAAGUCUGCAAAAUCAAAAGAAAAACAAGAAAAAAUUACAGACACAUUUAAAGUAAAAAGAAAAGUAGACCGUUUUAAUGGUGUUUCAGAAGCUGAACUUCUGACCAAGACUCUCCCCGAUAUUUUGACCUUCAAUCUGGACAUUGUCAUUAUUGGCAUAAACCCGGGACUAAUGGCUGCUUACAAAGGGCAUCAUUACCCUGGACCUGGAAACCAUUUUUGGAAGUGUUUGUUUAUGUCAGGGCUCAGUGAGGUCCAGCUGAACCAUAUGGAUGAUCACACUCUACCAGGGAAGUAUGGUAUUGGAUUUACCAACAUGGUGGAAAGGACCACGCCCGGCAGCAAAGAUCUCUCCAGUAAAGAAUUUCGUGAAGGAGGACGUAUUCUAGUACAGAAAUUACAGAAAUAUCAGCCACGAAUAGCAGUGUUUAAUGGAAAAUGUAUUUAUGAAAUUUUUAGUAAAGAAGUUUUUGGAGUAAAGGUUAAGAACUUGGAAUUUGGGCUUCAGCCCCAUAAGAUUCCAGACACAGAAACUCUCUGCUAUGUUAUGCCAUCAUCCAGUGCAAGAUGUGCUCAGUUUCCUCGAGCCCAAGACAAAGUUCAUUACUACAUAAAACUGAAGGACUUAAGAGAUCAGUUGAAAGGCAUUGAACGAAAUAUGGACGUUCAAGAGGUGCAAUAUACAUUUGACCUACAGCUUGCCCAAGAGGAUGCAAAGAAGAUGGCUGUUAAGGAAGAAAAAUAUGAUCCAGGUUAUGAGGCAGCAUAUGGUGGUGCUUACGGAGAAAAUCCAUGCAGCAGUGAACCUUGUGGCUUCUCUUCAAAUGGGCUAAUUGAGAGCGUGGAGUUAAGAGGAGAAUCAGCUUUCAGUGGCAUUCCUAAUGGGCAGUGGAUGACCCAGUCAUUUACAGACCAAAUUCCUUCCUUUAGUAAUCACUGUGGAACACAAGAACAGGAAGAAGAAAGCCAUGCUUAAGAAUGGUGCUUCUCAGCUCUGCUUAAAUGCUGCAGUUUUAAUGCAGUUGUCAACAAGUAGAACCUCAGUUUGCUAACUGAAGUGUUUUAUUAGUAUUUUACUCUAGUGGUGUAAUUGUAAUGUAGAACAGUUGUGUGGUAGUGUGAACCGUAUGAACCUAAGUAGUUUGGAAGAAAAAGUAGGGUUUUUGUAUACUAGCUUUUGUAUUUGAAUUAAUUAUCAUUCCAGCUUUUUAUAUACUAUAUUUCAUUUAUGAAGAAAUUGAUUUUCUUUUGGGAGUCACUUUUAAUCUGUAAUUUUAAAAUACAAGUCUGAAUAUUUAUAGUUGAUUCUUAACUGCAUAAACCUAGAUAUACCAUUAUCCCUUUUAUACCUAAGAAGGGCAUGCUAAUAAUUACCACUGUCAAAGAGGCAAAGGUGUUGAUUUUUGUAUAUGAAGUUAAGCCUCAGUGGAGUCUCAUUUGUUAGUUUUUAGUGGUAACUAAGGGUAAACUCAGGGUUCCCUGAGCUAUAUGCACACUCAGACCUCUUUGCUUUACCAGUGGUGUUUGUGAGUUGCUCAGUAGUAAAAACUGGCCCUUACCUGACAGAGCCCUGGCUUUGACCUGCUCAGCCCUGUGUGUUAAUCCUCUAGUAGCCAAUUAACUACUCUGGGGUGGCAGGUUCCAGAGAAUGCAGUAGACCUUUUGCCACUCAUCUGUGUUUUACUUGAGACAUGUAAAUAUGAUAGGGAAGGAACUGAAUUUCUCCAUUCAUAUUUAUAACCAUUCUAGUUUUAUCUUCCUUGGCUUUAAGAGUGUGCCAUGGAAAGUGAUAAGAAAUGAACUUCUAGGCUAAGCAAAAAGAUGCUGGAGAUAUUUGAUACUCUCAUUUAAACUGGUGCUUUAUGUACAUGAGAUGUACUAAAAUAAGUAAUAUAGAAUUUUUCUUGCUAGGUAAAUCCAGUAAGCCAAUAAUUUUAAAGAUUCUUUAUCUGCAUCAUUGCUGUUUGUUACUAUAAAUUAAAUGAACCUCAUGGAAAGGUUGAGGUGUAUACCUUUGUGAUUUUCUAAUGAGUUUUCCAUGGUGCUACAAAUAAUCCAGACUACCAGGUCUGGUAGAUAUUAAAGCUGGGUACUAAGAAAUGUUAUUUGCAUCCUCUCAGUUACUCCUGAAUAUUCUGAUUUCAUACGUACCCAGGGAGCAUGCUGUUUUGUCAAUCAAUAUAAAAUAUUUAUGAGGUCUCCCCCACCCCCAGGAGGUUAUAUGAUUGCUCUUCUCUUUAUAAUAAGAGAAACAAAUUCUUAUUGUGAAUCUUAACAUGCUUUUUAGCUGUGGCUAUGAUGGAUUUUAUUUUUUCCUAGGUCAAGCUGUGUAAAAGUCAUUUAUGUUAUUUAAAUGAUGUACUGUACUGCUGUUUACAUGGACGUUUUGUGCGGGUGCUUUGAAGUGCCUUGCAUCAGGGAUUAGGAGCAAUUAAAUUAUUUUUUCACGGGACUGUGUAAAGCAUGUAACUAGGUAUUGCUUUGGUAUAUAACUAUUGUAGCUUUACAAGAGAUUGUUUUAUUUGAAUGGGGAAAAUACCCUUUAAAUUAUGACGGACAUCCACUAGAGAUGGGUUUGAGGAUUUUCCAAGCGUGUAAUAAUGAUGUUUUUCCUAACAUGACAGAUGAGUAGUAAAUGUUGAUAUAUCCUAUACAUGACAGUGUGAGACUUUUUCAUUAAAUAAUAUUGAAAGAUUUUAAAAUUCAUUUGAAAGUCUGAUGGCUUUUACAAUAAAAGAUAUUAAGAAUUGUUAUCCUUAA